CGUCAGUCAGUCUGACGGUCAGUGGAUCGGUGGGUUUAUCUCAAGGCCUGAGUAGCCGGUAACAAACGAGGGUUCCCGGGAUUGGACCGACGCAGCCAUGGACUUCAUGAAUAACACUUCUUCAGAAUAUUUCCUGAUAUGACACUAUUGACCUGGGCACAAAAUUGUGAUUUGUGAAUAUUUAAAAUUCAUUGGCCGGGUGCGGGGGUUCACGCCUGUAAUCCUAGCACUUUGGGAGGCCGAGGCGGGCGGAUCACAAGGUCAGGAGAUCGAAACCAUCCUGGCUAACACGGUGAAACCCUGUCUCUACUGAAAAUACAAAAAAUUAGCUGGGCAUGGUAGCAUGCGCCUGUAGUCCCAGCUACUUGGGAGGCUGAGGCAGGAGAAUCGCUUGAACCCGGGAAGCAGAGGUUUCAGUGAGCAGAGAUCAGCGCCACUGCACUCCAGCCUGGACGACAGAGCGAGACUUCGCCACUGCACUCCAGCCUGGACGACAGAGCGAGACUUCGUCUCAAAAAGAAAAAAACCUCUGCGACUUGAUAUCAAAAGAAAGCUAACUGCUAGAUCUGAUCGAGUUAAGAGUGUGGAUCUGCAUCCUACAGAGCCAUGGAUGUUGGCAAGUCUUUACAAUGGCAGUGUGUGUGUUUGGAAUCAUGAAACACAGACACUGGUGAAGACAUUUGAAGUAUGUGAUCUUCCUGUUCGAGCUGCAAAGUUUGUUGCAAGGAAGAAUUGGGUUGUGACAGGAGCGGAUGACAUGCAGAUUAGAGUGUUCAAUUACAAUACUCUGGAGAGAGUUCAUAUGUUUGAAGCACACUCAGACUACAUUCGCUGUAUUGCUGUUCAUCCAACCCAGCCUUUCAUUCUAACUAGCAGUGAUGACAUGCUUAUUAAGCUCUGGGACUGGGAUAAAAAAUGGUCUUGCUCACAAGUGUUUGAAGGACACACCCAUUAUGUUAUGCAGAUUGUGAUCAACCCCAAAGAUAACAAUCAGUUUGCCAGUGCCUCUUUGGACAGGACUAUCAAGGUGUGGCAGUUGGGCUCUUCGUCACCAAACUUCACUUUGGAAGGACAUGAGAAAGGCGUGAAUUGCAUUGAUUACUACAGUGGUGGGGACAAGCCAUACCUCAUUUCAGGUGCAGAUGACCGUCUUGUUAAAAUAUGGGAUUAUCAGAAUAAAACAUGUGUGCAGACACUGGAAGGACAUGCCCAAAAUGUGUCUUGUGCCAGCUUUCAUCCUGAGUUGCCAAUCAUUAUCACAGGUUCAGAAGAUGGAACAGUACGUAUUUGGCAUUCAAGCACCUACCGGCUUGAGAGCACACUGAAUUAUGGAAUGGAGAGGGUAUGGUGCGUGGCCAGUCUAAGAGGGUCAAACAAUGUCGCUUUGGGCUAUGAUGAAGGGAGCAUCAUUGUUAAGCUUGGUCGGGAGGAACCUGCCAUGUCCAUGGAUGCCAAUGGAAAGAUAAUUUGGGCCAAGCAUUCAGAAGUCCAGCAGGCCAACCUAAAAGCAAUGGGAGAUGCUGAAAUUAAAGAUGGUGAAAGAUUGCCACUGGCAGUAAAGGAUAUGGGCAGUUGUGAAAUAUACCCUCAGACUAUUCAGCACAAUCCUAAUGGGCGGUUUGUGGUGGUGUGUGGUGAUGGGGAGUAUAUCAUCUACACAGCAAUGGCAUUGAGAAACAAGAGCUUUGGAUCUGCUCAGGAGUUUGCAUGGGCCCACGAUUCUUCAGAGUAUGCAAUAAGAGAGAGCAACAGCAUUGUAAAGAUAUUUAAGAACUUUAAGGAAAAAAAAUCAUUUAAACCAGAUUUUGGAGCAGAAAGUAUCUACGGCGGCUUCUUAUUGGGAGUCAGAUCUGUAAAUGGCUUAGCCUUCUAUGACUGGGACAAUACAGAACUCAUACGAAGAAUUGAAAUUCAGCCCAAACAUAUUUUCUGGUCUGACUCUGGAGAGCUAGUCUGUAUUGCUACUGAGGAAUCAUUUUUUAUCCUUAAGUAUCUGUCAGAAAAAGUCUUGGCUGCACAGGAAACACAUGAGGGAGUUACUGAAGAUGGCAUUGAAGAUGCCUUUGAGGUUCUUGGUGAGAUUCAGGAAAUUGUGAAAACAGGGCUUUGGGUAGGCGAUUGCUUCAUUUACACAAGUUCUGUGAACAGAUUAAAUUAUUAUGUUGGAGGAGAAAUAGUCACCAUUGCCCACUUGGACAGGACGAUGUAUCUCCUAGGCUACAUUCCUAAAGACAACAGGCUUUAUCUGGGGGAUAAAGAAUUGAACAUCAUUAGCUAUUCCCUGCUGGUUUCAGUCCUGGAAUACCAGACAGCUGUCAUGCGGAGGGACUUUAGCAUGGCUGAUAAGGUCCUUCCUACCAUUCCAAAAGAACAGAGGACCAGAGUUGCACACUUUUUGGAAAAGCAGGGCUUCAAGCAGCAAGCUCUUACAGUAUCCACAGAUCCUGAGCAUCGUUUUGAGCUUGCUCUUCAGCUUGGAGAGUUAAAAAUUGCAUACCAGUUAGCAGUGGAAGCAGAGUCAGAACAGAAGUGGAAACAACUUGCUGAACUUGCCAUUAGUAAAUGUCAGUUUGGCCUAGCCCAGGAGUGCCUGCAUCAUGCACAGGAUUAUGGGGGCCUGCUGCUUUUGGCCACUGCCUCUGGAAAUGCUAAUAUGGUGAACAAGCUAGCAGAGGGUGCGGAGAGAGAUGGCAAAAAUAAUGUGGCAUUCAUGAGCUACUUUUUACAGGGCAAGGUUGAUGCCUGCCUAGAGCUCUUAAUUAGAACUGGACGGCUGCCAGAAGCUGCCUUCUUGGCCCGAACUUACUUACCCAGUCAGGUUUCAAGGGUAGUGAAACUCUGGAGAGAGAAUCUCUCAAAAGUCAAUCAGAAAGCAGCAGAAUCCCUUGCUGACCCAACAGAGUAUGAAAACCUGUUCCCUGGAUUAAAAGAAGCCUUUGUUGUUGAAGAAUGGGUGAAGGAAACACAUGCUGAUCUGUGGCCAGCCAAACAAUACCCACUUGUCACGCCAAAUGAAGAGAGAAAUGUCAUGGAAGAGGGAAAAGACUUUCAGCCCUCAAGAUCUACAGCUCAACAGGAACUUGAUGGGAAACCUGCUUCUCCUACUCCGGUUAUUGUGGCCUCCCACACAGCCAACAAAGAAGAAAAGAGUUUACUCGAACUAGAAGUAGAUUUGGAUAAUUUGGAAUUAGAAGAUAUUGACACAACAGAUAUCAAUCUGGAUGAAGAUAUUUUGGAUGAUUGACUGUAAUGCUUUCCAUUUACCUGACUAAACAGAUCAUUAUUAUAUAUAGGUAUUGAUUGCUACCCUGACCACAGUGCUUUGGACUAUGAGAAACUUCUUAGAUUUUUAUAUGUAAAUGCUGUGGACCACUGGGAGCACAAUGCCCACAUCAUCUUAAGAAGAGUUUAUGUGCAGCAUUUAAAUCACUGUGUUUUCCUUGUUAACUAAAACAGACAUGGGCUUUGAUUUUUUUCAUACUAUUAGACCAUAUCUCAUAAAACCUUUUGAAUUAAUGAAGGUACUUGUUUCCUUUCUCAAUAAUGAAAAUAGGCUUCUAGUUUUAGAAGGCUGAGCCGAAACUACACCUUGCCUAGGGAUCAGCCCCACUGUCUUUUCUUUGUAUAACUAAAUCUGCAUUUUCAAAUGUUGUCAAUCACAUUUUUCUUAGAGCUGAAUAUCCAGGCUGUAAUUCUCUAAA